GCAGCUGCCGCGGCGCCCGAAUCCCGGCGGCCGCCGCGCUUUCCCGCUUCGCGGAGACCGACGCAGGCGCCCGCCCCCGAGGCCGAAGGGCACUGGGCGGCGAGGGCUGCGGUAGCUGGCGACUCCGGGGGCGUCUGCGCGGCGCGCGCUAGACGAGGCUGCCCCGGCGGCCACCCCGCGACCCCGCGUCGCCGGGAUUUGCGCGCGGAGAACGCCGGUUCUGGAGGGAGCACGCCUCCCCAAAGUGCAGAGGAGGGUCCGGCGGCGCGUCUCCGCGGAAACCCUCUCCACUGUAGUUACCCCGGAUGCCGACUUAGUAGUUUGUUUUCCGAGAAAAGAGAGGGGAUCUGGGCAGAAGGGCCCCGUUUGCCCCAAAAGAAGGUGCAAGGAUCAGAAGAUAACGAAACGUCCACUUCCUGAAGGGUGGGAAAAAAAGAAAAAGAAAAAGGAGCCACCCACGCUGGAGAUGUCCGUUUUAGAUCUUCUUAUUUUCUUCCCUUUCGCUUCGGUUUUUCUUCUCGAGGCUCAUUUAAUCUGCUAGAGAAGGAGGAGGAGCAGAAGAUGGGGGCCGAGGAGGAGGGGAAGAGAAAGAGAAGUUUGCCAAGAAUAAAGUUUUUGCCGGCAAGCGCGGGGACUCCGCAGUGGAGGGCACUGCGGAGUCUCGGGGAGUCACAGCGGGGGCCUCGGGCCCAAAUGCCUCUGCCCGGAGCUCGAGCCGACACACACACUCAGUCCGACCCCUCUUUGUUCCCGGCUCGAGUUUCUCAGCCUGGCUCGCCGGCUCGCCGCUCUGCACGCCUCCGCCGGCCAGCUCUGUCAAAGCAAAGAGCUGCGCCCCUUGAGUUCGCCCGGCCGAGGGGAGGGGACGCCCCGAGCUUGGCCGCGUGCGAGGCUCCGGGCGCGUCCUGGUUCCUCGGCCCGAGAGCGCGCAGCCCGGGUCCCUCCUCCGCGCCCUGCCCCGCAGAUCCUGUAGGACGAGUCUUGGUUUUGGGGUGUGUGAGUGUGGUGUGUGCGCGCGCGCCUGGAGGGAAGGAUCAGGCAACUUGGCGAGAGAAGGAAGGACCGGGCGCUGCUUAUAACCCACCGAAAGGCACGCUUUGCCCGCGUGAAACUGACAAGAAACAUUGCCGCAGUGGCUUGACUUCAUCAUCUAAGUAUCUAUUUACUUGGCCCCCACCCACCCACUCCUUUUCCUCUGCCAGUCUCUCCCCUACCUCCUUGACGCCUCCCACUCUCCCUCCCUGGCUCUGGCAGAGGGAGGAAGAUGAAAGAGAAAGCCGCUGCCGCUGUGAUGGACACCACAUUGAUAGAUGCUCUGACAGUGGGGAGAGGCGGGAAUCUGGGACUGAGAAAAAAAGGAAAAGGGGAAAAUAUAACAGACAUUGCUCAACUAUUAAGAGAGAACAGAAGGACAAGGAAAAGAGAGUUGUAGCUUUCCCGAAUAUAAUAUCACACACACGCUCUUUGGAGACAAGGGAACACACUAGUGAAAAUAAAAUCUCUAGGCUUACGGAGAAAAAAUAUGACGAGGAAGAAGGAACUGAAGACUAGAUUUUAAUUAUUGCUUUUUAAACAAUAUAUCUUUCAUUCUGUUCUCACCACGGGAUGUACGGAGAGUUGUGCUAGGUCUCCAGUGGGUUUUCAGAGACACACACCGCAGUGUGUGGGAACCUCAUCGAGAAUGAAAAGAUAAUCCAAGAAGGGGGAAGAGAAGGCAAAAGGACUCAGGAGAGCAAAGCCAGAAGAGGGAGGGAGGACGGGGUAGUCCCUGGCACCUUGGACUGCGAACUGAAAGGGACCCUUGAAGACACCAAUCCGAAUACAACCUCAAAAAUUCCCCAGUCUCCACUGUCUCUUUGAUGAAUUUUGUACAAAGACAGGAGUUUUCAGGAGAUACUUUGUGAAAGUUACAGCAGAAGGGAAGCUGAAGUUUGAAAACACAUUACAUUUUGUCCCUUGGUUCUCAAACCCCCUCAGUUAAAAAUCUAGGCAAAAUUAUUAUAUCCAAUACAGUAACCAUCUGUAAAACUUCAGAACAGUAAACAAAGGACAUAAAGAAAUGUAUCUUCAUCUCCCUUAAAUCGAAAACAAGCAAAACACUACAGAAUCAGAUUUUGCUCCAUUAUAUAGGAAUUGUCUGGCAAAGAUCCCUCUUUUUUUCCUAAAGGUGAAAUUUCAGGCUGCUGAACAUUGAAUGGGUAAAGAUUUUUACAAUGCUGUAUCUAAGUGAGCACUAAUGACUUCACCUACUAAUAACGACUACUUCUUGGGAAUAAGAAUUUACUAGGAAGCAAUUUUUAAAACUUUACAAAGGAUCCAAUUGGUCCCUACAACAUGGCCAGUAGUCACAUGUAAAUUCUAUCUGGAAGAUUGGGGUGAAAUUAAGGGGUUGGUGAAGGAAUCCAGGAAAAUUAAAACAUUAAAUCCAUUUUUAAUAGCUGACAAUGCUAUGCCUCAAGAGAAGAAAAAGAGUAUAUUCUGCUACAGUGUGUGAGAAACCCAAUUUUUGUUUUUGGAUGAUGGUGGUAUGUCACUUCCCUUAAAGUUAGGCACCAGUGUGAGUAGUGUCCCAGAGAGGUGAACGUGUAGCUGUGUCAGACAUUUAUAGCCCCAUUCUUAAAAGACACAUGGGAAAACAGUCAAAAGUCCUCCCAUAACUGCACCAAUUUGACCAAUAGGAAAACAAGUGGAAAAUGCAGUUUCACCAAAGCAGAGUAGAGGUUCCUUUUCAUCAAACCCUCAGGAGGGGGAGGGGAGAACACAGAAUGGCCAGGGGGUACUUUCUGGAAGCCGAAGAGAGAUUAAAUGAUGACUCUUACAUCCCC